CUUUCUCUCCUGCUCUCGCGGCGGGAACGCGGGGCCUCCGUGUUCUGCUGUCUUCAUCAGCGUGGGCCGCGGGUAGCGGGUAGUGGGGUGGCUGGGUUUGGGCUUUCCAGAGAAGGUGACGCUGCCUGAGCUGAGCUUAAAGCACGCCCAGGAGUUAGACUAGGAGAGGGUCGUGUGGGGGAAAGAAGGGCGUUCUGGGCAUCGGUAAAUUCCCAGAGAGGAUGGAGAGCUCAGUGAUCUCCAGAAAGUGAAAGAGGCGGGGAGUGGGCCAUCGGAGGAGGCUGCCCAGGGUGUAAGAGCGACCGAUUGGUAGGGAAGCUUUUGUAAUAAUCCAAUCAAGUGAUAAUGUGAACUUGAAUUAAGGCUGGCAGUAUGGAUGGCGAGGAAGGGACAAAUUGUGAAGCAGCUAGGCGGUAUAGUCGACCUAGAGGGUGAUUGAAUUUGAAAGAGGUUCCUAGGCCGGGCGCGGUGGCUCACGCCUGUAAUCCCAGCACUUUGGGAGGCCGAGGCGGGCGGAUUACCUGAGGUCCGGAGUUCAAAACCAGCCUGGCCAACAUGGUGAAACCCCGUCUCUACUAAAAGUACAAAAAAAAUUAGCUGGGUAUGGUGCGGGCGCCUGUAAUCCCACUACUUGGGAGGCUGAGGCAGGAGAAUCGCUUGAACCUGGGAGGCAGAGGUUGCGGUGAGCCGAGAUCACGCCAUUUUGCACUUCAGCCUAGGCAACAAGAGCGAAACUCCGUCUCAAAAAAAAAAAAAAAAAAAAAAUUCCUAUUGGAGACUAGUCCCUCCGUAAACACUACGAUUCCCAUCCACCUCUGCCUUCCAGUGCUCCUUUGUUACUCAUUGUUUAUAGUUAAUCUUCAGCUUCUCUCAACUGAGCCCAUUUCAUCAUUAUUCAGAACUGCUUGGGCCGGGCGCAGUGGCUUAUGGCCUGUAAUCAUCUUAGGAGGCCAAGGUGGGAGGAUCGCUUGACCCUAGGAGUUCAAGACUAGCCUGGGCAACAUAGUGAAACCUUGUCUCUACAAAAAGAAAAUUAAAAAUUAGUUGGGCAUGGUGGUGCGCACCUGUAGUCCCAGCUACAGGAGGCUGAGGUGAGAGGAUGGCUUGAGCCCAGGAGGUCGAGGCUGCAGUGAGCCAUGUUCUUAUUGCACUCCAGCCUGAGUGGCAGAGCAGCAAAGUGAGGGACACACUGUCUCUAAAAACAAAACAAACAAACAAAAAAAAAACAAAAAUAAAAAAACUCUUUGGAUUUCUCCUAUCCUAAAAAAGGGAAACUCUUUUGACUAUCCCCCAUCCCAUUAAUUCAUUUAACAGGUAUCUAUUGUGUACAGUUUACCUGGCACUGACUUUGGACACACACCAAUCAACAAGAGAAUCAGUCCUUGCACUCAAGUCGUUUUUUACAGUCAAAUUCAGGAAGUACACACUGAUGGAAAGAAUCAAAGUAAUGUAAAAUUACAUUAGGUAAGAGCUACAAGGCAGAAAUAUGUGAUAGGAUAAGAUGAGGGGACCUGAUUUGGACAUUUCAGUCAAGACUUGAAAAAUGAUAAGGUGUUAGGUAAAAGCAUAAAAGAGUCCAAACAGAGGAAAUGGAUUGUGUGAGGCCCCAAGGUGGGCAGACACACUUGAGGUGUUUAAGCAACUAAAUUCAGUCAACCUUGGCUAGAGCAUAGUGAGGGGAUGAGGCGGAUGGUGCCCGGAUCACUGGACCUGCAAGGCUGUAGUAAGAGGACUGCCUUCUAAGAGCAAGGGUGUGGCAGCCAAAUCCCUCCAAUGGCCUAUAAGGCCAUCAUGAGGAAGCCACGAGCAGCCGUGGGAAGUGGUCACAGGAAGCAGGCAGCCAGCCAGGAAGGGAGGCAGAAGCAUGCUAAGAACAACAGUCAGGCCAAGCCUUCUGCCUGUGAUGGCCUGGCCAGGCAGCCGGAAGAGGUGGUAUUGCAGGCCUCUGUCUCCUCAUACCAUCUAUUCAGAGACGUAGCUGAAGUCACAGCCUUCCGAGGGAGCCUGCUAAGCUGGUACGACCAAGAGAAACGGGACCUACCAUGGAGAAGACGGGCAGAAGAUGAGAUGGACCUGGACAGGCGGGCAUAUGCUGUGUGGGUCUCAGAGGUCAUGCUGCAGCAGACCCAGGUUGCCACUGUGAUCAACUACUAUACCGGAUGGAUGCAGAAGUGGCCUACACUGCAGGACCUGGCCAGUGCUUCCCUGGAGGAGGUGAAUCAACUCUGGGCUGGCCUGGGCUACUAUUCUCGUGGCCGGCGGCUGCAGGAGGGAGCUCGGAAGGUGGUAGAGGAGCUAGGGGGCCACAUGCCACGUACAGCAGAGACCCUGCAGCAGCUCCUGCCUGGCGUGGGGCGCUACACAGCUGGGGCCAUUGCCUCUAUCGCCUUUGGCCAGGCAACCGGUGUGGUGGAUGGCAACGUAGCACGGGUGCUGUGCCGUGUCCGAGCCAUUGGUGCUGAUCCCAGCAGCACCCUUGUUUCCCAGCAGCUCUGGGGUCUAGCCCAGCAGCUGGUGGACCCAGCCCGGCCAGGAGAUUUCAACCAAGCAGCCAUGGAGCUAGGGGCCACAGUGUGUACCCCACAGCGCCCACUGUGCAGCCAGUGCCCUGUGGAGAGCCUGUGCCGGGCACGCCAGAGAGUGGAGCAGGAACAGCUCUUAGCCUCAGGGAGCCUGUCGGGCAGUCCUGACGUGGAGGAGUGUGCUCCCAACACUGGACAGUGCCACCUGUGCCUGCCUCCCUCGGAGCCCUGGGACCAGACCCUGGGAGUGGUCAACUUCCCCAGAAAGGCCAGCCGCAAGCCCCCCAGGGAGGAGAGCUCUGCCACCUGUGUUCUGGAACAGCCUGGGGCCCUUGGGGCCCAAAUUCUGCUGGUGCAGAGGCCCAACUCAGGUCUGCUGGCAGGACUGUGGGAGUUCCCGUCCGUGACCUGGGAGCCCUCAGAGCAGCUUCAGCGCAAGGCCCUGCUGCAGGAACUACAGCGUUGGGCUGGGCCCCUCCCAGCCACGCACCUCCGGCACCUUGGGGAGGUUGUCCACACCUUCUCUCACAUCAAGCUGACAUAUCAAGUAUAUGGGCUGGCCUUGGAAGGGCAGACCCCAGUGACCACCGUACCACCAGGUGCUCGCUGGCUGACGCAGGAGGAAUUUCACACCGCAGCUGUUUCCACCGCCAUGAAAAAGGUUUUCCGUGUGUAUCAGGGCCAACAGCCAGGGACCUGUAUGGGUUCCAAAAGGUCCCAGGUGUCCUCUCCGUGCAGUCGGAAAAAGCCCCGCAUGGGCCAGCAAGUCCUGGAUAAUUUCUUUCGGUCUCACAUCUCCACUGAUGCACACAGCCUCAACAGUGCAGCCCAGUGACACCUCUGAAAGCCCCCAUUCCCUGAGAAUCCUGUUGUUAGUAAAGUGCUUAUUUUUGUAGUUA